AUGGAUCUGGGAUCAGGCAGCAGCCAGGGUGGGGACUUGGAGACCACCUUCCAGCUGUGGCUGCAGCUGCUCCUCUGGGCCCACCUGGCUGUACGUUUCCUGGGCUACCUGCACCGCACCUUCCGGGGGCCUAAGCCACAGCCAGCACCCUGA